AGCACCCACGAUGCGGGACCUGCCUCUCACCAGCCUGGCCCUAGUGCUGUCUGCCCUGGGGGCUCUGCUGGGGACUGAGGCCCUCAGAGCAGAGGAGCCAGCUGUGGGCACCAGUGGCCUCAUCUUCCGAGAAGACUUGGACUGGCCUCCAGGCAGCCCACAAGAGCCUCUGUGCCUGGUGGCACUGGGCGGGGACAGCAAUGGCAGCAGCUCCCCCCUGCGGGUGGUGGGGGCUCUAAGCGCCUAUGAGCAGGCCUUCCUGGGGGCCGUGCAGAGGGCCCGCUGGGGCCCCCGAGACCUGGCCACCUUCGGGGUCUGCAACACCGGUGACAGGCAGGCUGCCUUGCCCUCUCUACGGCGGCUGGGGGCCUGGCUGCGGGACCCUGGGGGGCAGCGCCUGGUGGUCCUACACCUGGAGGAAGUGACCUGGGAGCCAACACCCUCGCUGAGGUUCCAGGAGCCCCCGCCUGGAGGAGCUGGCCCCCCAGAGCUGGCGCUGCUGGUGCUGUACCCUGGGCCUGGCCCUGAGGUCACUGUGACGAGGGCUGGGCUGCCGGGUGCCCAGAGCCUCUGCCCCUCCCGAGACACCCGCUACCUGGUGUUAGCGGUGGACCGCCCUGCGGGGGCCUGGCGCGGCUCCGGGCUGGCCUUGACCCUGCAGCCCCGCGGAGAGGACUCCCGGCUGAGUACCGCCCGGCUGCAGGCACUGCUGUUCGGCGACGACCACCGCUGCUUCACACGGAUGACCCCGGCCCUGCUCCUGCUGCCGCGGUCCGAGCCCGCGCCGCUGCCUGCGCACGGCCAGCUGGACACCGUGCCCUUCCCGCCGCCCAGGCCAUCCGCGGAACUCGAGGAGUCGCCACCCAGCGCAGACCCCUUCCUGGAGACGCUCACGCGCCUGGUGCGGGCGCUGCGGGUCCCCCCGGCCCGGGCCUCCGCGCCGCGCCUGGCCCUGGAUCCGGACGCGCUGGCCGGCUUCCCGCAGGGCCUAGUCAACCUGUCGGACCCCGCGGCGCUGGAGCGCCUACUCGACGGCGAGGAGCCGCUGCUGCUGCUGCUGAGGCCCACUGCGGCCACCACCGGGGAUCCUGCGCCCCUGCACGACCCCACGUCGGCGCCGUGGGCCACGGCCCUGGCGCGCCGCGUGGCUGCUGAACUGCAAGCGGCGGCUGCCGAGCUGCGAAGCCUCCCGGGUCUGCCUCCGGCCACAGCCCCGCUGCUGGCGCGCCUGCUCGCGCUCUGCCCAGGUGGCCCCGGCGGCCUCGGCGAUCCCCUGCGAGCGCUGCUGCUCCUGAAGGCGCUGCAGGGCCUGCGCGUGGAGUGGCGCGGGCGGGAUCCGCGCGGGCCGGGUCGGGCACAGCGCAGCGCGGGGGCCACCGCCGCCGACGGGCCGUGCGCGCUGCGCGAGCUCAGCGUAGACCUCCGCGCCGAGCGCUCCGUACUCAUCCCCGAGACCUACCAGGCCAACAAUUGCCAGGGCGUGUGCGGCUGGCCUCAGUCCGACCGCAACCCGCGCUACGGCAACCACGUGGUGCUGCUGCUGAAGAUGCAGGUCCGUGGGGCCGCCCUGGCGCGCCCACCCUGCUGCGUGCCCACCGCCUACGCGGGCAAGCUGCUCAUCAGCCUGUCGGAGGAGCGCAUCAGCGCGCACCACGUGCCCAACAUGGUGGCCACCGAGUGUGGCUGCCGGUGACCCCUGCGCCGCGCGGACUCCUGCCCCGAGGGUCCGGACGCGCCCCAGCUCGCGCCCCUUCCCAUAUUUAUUCGGACCCCAAGCAUCGCCCCAAUAAAGACCAGCAAGCAACCGGC